AACGGAAGUGUGGCGGCGUUGGGUUGAGCGGGCUUUUUGGAAGUUUGUGGCGGAGGUGAGGCCGAGGUGACUGCAGAGCGGCUCGCGAGGGUUUUGGACUGAUAAAGCAAUGGAAGCCACUGAAGAGCUUUAAGAUGAGGAUGGCAUGGAGGGAAGAUAAGUCACAUAAUCAGGUUUGUGUUUCAAAAACAUCACUUUAGUUGCUGCGUAGAAGGGAACAAGUUAGGAAACGAUUGCAGUAGUUCAGGUGAGAGAUGGUGGUGGCUUGGGGUAAUGUGUCAGUAGUGGAGAUGGAGAAAAGUAGACAGAUUUGGGAGAUAUUUAGUAGGUAACAUUGACAGGACUUGGUAAUGGAUGUGGUGAAGGAUGAAGGCAAAGUUGUUAAGAAUGUUACCUAGGUUUCUGGUCUGAGCAGCUGAGUGGAUGAUGGUACCAUUUAUGGAGACGGGAAACACAGGAGGAAGAAGAGGAGGAACAGAUUUUCUUUCUACUAGGCUGUACUUCCCCCUUCUAUUUUCAUAGCUACUCACUGAAUUCUAUCUGCUUCAUGUGCCUCCAUUUCAUCCCAUCUUUUCUGUUCUCCAGUCACCACCCUAGUACAGGUCUUUAUCAUUUCCACUAAAAUAACUUCCAAAUGGUCUCUUAGCAUUUGCUGUUUCUUCUUACCUUCUCCCCACUUUAAUCUGCACAAAGAUGCUAGGUUCUGUUUCCUCAAACACUUGCAAUCUUGUGAGAUUGUCUUUUGCUCAAAUUUUUUAAUGGUUCUCAGUAAUUUACGAAAUAGAAUCUAAAUUCCUUAACCUGUUUACUUCCAGCCUAUCUUUCCAGACUUCCUACUCACUAUUUUCCUACUUGGAUUCUACCUCAGCCAUUUUACUCAUUUUCCCCCAAAGAAAUUUCUCAUUUCCCGUAUGAAUGCCUUUGUUCAUGAUACCCUUCUCCAUAAUGUAUACAACCUGGUUGUCUGGACUACCUAUAUUUAAUCUCUAAGUUCCAGUUCAAGCUUUCCUCUGCUGCGAAACCUUGACAUUUAAGAACACAGUUACAUCUUUUACCUUGUUAACUUCUCAGCUUUUCUUUCUUUCUUUCUUCCUUUCUUUUUUUUUUUUUUUUUUUUGAGACAGAGCCUCGCUCUGUCGCCCAGGCUGGAGUGCAGUGGCGUGAUCUCCGCUCACUGCAAGCUCCUCCUCCCGGGUUCACGCCAUUCUCCUGCCUCAGCCUCCCGAGUAGCUGGGACUAUAGGCGCCCGCCACCACGCCCAGCUAAUUUUUUUUUGUAUUUUUGGUAGAGACGGGGGUUUCACCGUGUUAGCCAAAAUGGUCUCGAUCUCCUGACUUCGUGAUCUGCCCUCCUCAGCCUCCCAAAGUGCUGGGAUUACAGGCAUGAGCCACGGUGCCGGCCUCUUUUUUUUUUUUUUUUUAAGAGACAGGGUCUUACCUUGUUGCCUAGGCUGGAGUACUGUGGCAUGAUCAUAGCUCACUGCAGCCUCACACUCUUGGGCUCCCCUUCUCACUUGUUUUUAUACCAUUUAAUUGGCACAUAGCAUUUAUAGUGCUAUUGGUUUAUUCAUUUAUUUGUCAAAUACUUUAUUACAUGCUUAUGGUAAUAUAUAAUGUAUUACAUACUUGAUAUGCUGUUAAAUGGAAGCUUUGUUCUAGGUAGUAUGGUGAGUAGAUGGUAACAAGUGUGGGCAAAAAUUAUGAAACCACUUGAUUAGAAUACAGAUUCCUAAUAAGGCAAUUCCAGGGAAUUUUCAGGAUUAUUUUGGUUAGGUUAAGAAUCAUCUUGCCACUGAGCUUAAGAAGAAGAAGAAAAAAGAAUCAGCUACUUAAAGAUAGUCCUAAGUUUGUUGAGCACCCAUUGCAUAAUAGUUCUGUGAUAUGAGCAACAAUGGACCAGAAGAUUUUAUCUCUAGCAGCAGAAAAAACAGCAGACAAACUGCAAGAAUUUCUUCAAACCCUGAGAGAAGGUGAUUUGACUAAUCUCCUUCAGAAUCAAGCAGUGAAAGGAAAAGUUGCUGGAGCACUCCUGAGAGCCAUCUUCAAAGGUUCCCCCUGCUCUGAGGAAGCUGGAACACUUAGGAGACGUAAGAUAUACACUUGUUGUAUCCAGUUGGUGGAAUCGGGGGAUUUGCAGAAAGAAAUAGCGUCUGAGAUCAUAGGAUUACUGAUGCUGGAGGCUCACCAUUUUCCAGGACCAUUAUUGGUUGAAUUAGCCAAUGAGUUUAUUAGUGCUGUCAGAGAAGGCAGCCUAGUGAAUGGAAAAUCUUUGGAGUUACUACCUAUCAUUCUCACUGCCCUGGCUACGAAAAAGGAAAAUCUGGCUUAUGGAAAAGGUGUACUGAGUGGGGAAGAAUGUAAGAAACAGUUGAUUAACACCCUGUGUUCUGGCAGGUGGGAUCAGCAAUAUGUAAUCCAACUCACCUCCAUGUUCAAGGAUGUCCCUCUGACUGCAGAAGAGGUGGAAUUUGUGGUGGAAAAAGCAUUGAGCAUGUUCUCCAAGAUGAAUCUUCAAGAAAUACCACCUUUGGUCUAUCAGCUUCUGGUUCUCUCCUCCAAGGGAAGCAGAAAGAGUGUUUUGGAAGGAAUCAUAGCCUUCUUCAGUGCACUAGAUAAGCAGCACAAUGAGGAACAGAGUGGUGACGAGCUAUUGGAUGUUGUCACUGUGCCAUCAGGUGAACUUCGUCAUGUGGAAGGCACCAUUAUUCUACACAUUGUGUUUGCCAUCAAAUUGGACUAUGAACUAGGCAGAGAACUCGUGAAACACUUAAAGGUAGGACAGCAAGGAGAUUCCAAUAAUAACUUAAGUCCCUUCAGCAUUGCUCUUCUUCUGUCUGUAACAAGAAUACAAAGAUUUCAGGACCAGGUGCUUGAUCUUUUAAAGACUUCGGUUGUAAAGAGCUUUAAGGAUCUUCAACUCCUCCAAGGCUCAAAAUUUCUUCAGAAUCUAGUUCCUCAUAGAUCUUAUGUUUCAACCAUGAUCUUGGAAGUAGUGAAGAAUAGCGUUCAUAGCUGGGACCAUGUUACUCAGGGCCUCGUAGAACUUGGUUUCAUUUUGAUGGAUUCAUAUGGGCCAAAGAAGGUUCUUGAUGGAAAAACUAUUGAAACCAGCCCAAGUCUUUCUAGAAUGCCAAACCAGCAUGCAUGUAAGCUCGGAGCUAAUAUCCUGUUGGAAACUUUUAAGAUCCAUGAGAUGAUCAGACAAGAAAUUUUGGAGCAGGUCCUCAACAGGGUUGUUACCAGAGCAUCUUCUCCCAUCAGUCAUUUCUUAGACCUGCUUUCAAAUAUCGUCAUGUAUGCACCCUUAGUUCUUCAAAGUUGUUCUUCUAAAGUCACAGAAGCUUUUGACUAUUUGUCCUUUCUGCCCCUUCAGACUGUACAAAGGCUGCUUAAGGCAGUGCAGCCCCUUCUCAAAGUCAGCAUGUCAAUGAGAGACUGCUUGAUACUUGUCCUUCGGAAAGCUAUGUUUGCCAACCAGCUUGAUGCCCGAAAAUCUGCAGUUGCUGGGUUUUUGCUGCUCCUGAAGAACUUUAAAGUUUUAGGCAGCCUGUCAUCCUCUCAGUGCAGUCAGUCUCUCAGUGUCAGUCAGGUUCAUGUGGAUGUUCACAGCCAUUACAAUUCUGUCGCCAAUGAAACUUUUUGCCUUGAGAUCAUGGAUAGUUUGAGGAGAUGCUUAAGCCAGCAAGCUGAUGUUCGACUCAUGCUUUAUGAGGGGUUUUAUGAUGUUCUUCGAAGGAACUCUCAGCUGGCUAAUUCAGUCAUGCAAACUCUGCUCUCACAGUUAAAACAGUUCUAUGAGCCAAAACCUGAUCUGCUGCCUCCUCUGAAAUUAGAAGCUUGUAUUCUGACCCAAGGAGAUAAGAUCUCUCUACAAGAACCACUGGAUUAUCUGCUGUGUUGUAUUCAGCAUUGUUUGGCCUGGUAUAAGAAUACAGUCAUACCCUUACAGCAGGGAGAGGAGGAAGAGGAGGAGGAAGAGGCAUUCUACGAAGACCUAGAUGAUAUAUUGGAGUCCAUUACUAAUAGAAUGAUUAAGAGUGAGCUGGAAGACUUUGAACUGGAUAAAUCAGCAGAUUUUUCUCAGAGCACCAGUAUUGGCAUAAAAAAUAAUAUCUGUGCUUUUCUUGUGAUGGGAGUUUGUGAGGUUUUAAUAGAAUACAAUUUCUCCAUAAGUAGUUUCAGUAAGAAUAGGUUUGAGGACAUUCUGAGCUUAUUUAUGUGUUACAAAAAACUCUCUGACAUUCUUAAUGAAAAAGCGGGUAAAGCCAAAACUAAAAUGGCCAACAAGACAAGUGAUAGUCUUUUGUCCAUGAAAUUUGUGUCCAGUCUUCUCACUGCUCUUUUCAGGGAUAGUAUCCAAAGCCACCAAGAAAGCCUUUCUGUUCUCAGGUCCAGCAAUGAGUUUAUGCGCUAUGCAGUGAAUGUAGCUCUGCAGAAAGUACAGCAGCUAAAGGAAACAGGGCAUGUGAGUGGCCCUGAUGGCCAAAACCCAGAAAAGAUCUUUCAGAACCUCUGUGACAUAACUCGAGUCUUGCUAUGGAGAUACACUUCAAUUCCUACUUCAGUGGAAGAGUCGGGAAAGAAAGAGAAAGGAAAGAGCAUCUCACUGCUGUGCUUGGAGGGUUUACAGAAAAUAUUCAGUGCUGUGCAACAGUUCUAUCAGCCCAAGAUUCAGCAGUUUCUCAGAGCUCUGGAUGUCACAGAUAAGGAAGGAGAAGAGAGAGAAGAUGCAGAUGUCAGUGUCACUCAGAGAACAGCAUUCCAGAUCCGGCAAUUUCAGAGGUCCUUGUUGAAUUUACUUAGCAGUCAAGAGGAAGAUUUUAAUAGCAAAGAAGCCCUCCUGCUAGUCACGGUUCUUACCAGUUUGUCCAAGUUACUGGAGCCCUCCUCUCCUCAGUUUGUGCAGAUGUUAUCCUGGACAUCAAAGAUUUGCAAGGAAAACAGCCGGGAGGAUGCCUUGUUUUGCAAGAGCUUGAUGAACUUGCUCUUCAGCCUGCAUGUUUCGUAUAAGAGUCCUGUCAUUCUGCUGCGUGACUUGUCCCAGGAUAUCCACGGGCAUCUGGGAGAUAUAGACCAGGAUGUAGAGGUGGAGAAAACAAACCACUUUGCAAUAGUGAAUUUGAGAACGGCUGCCCCCACUGUCUGUUUACUUGUUCUGAGUCAGGCCGAGAAGGUUCUAGAAGAAGUGGACUGGCUAAUCACCAAGCUUAAGGGACAAGUGAGCCAAGAAACCUUAUCAGAAGAGGCCUCUUCUCAGGCAACCCUACCAAAUCAGCCUGUUGAGAAAGCUAUCAUCAUGCAACUGGGAACUCUGCUUACAUUUUUCCACGAGCUGGUGCAGACAGCUCUGCCAUCAGGCAGCUGUGUGGACACCUUGUUAAAGGACUUGUGCAAAAUGUACACCACACUUACAGCCCUUGUCAGAUAUUAUCUCCAGGUGUGUCAGAGCUCCGGAGGAAUUCCAAAAAAUAUGGAAAAGCUGGUGAAGCUGUCUGGUUCUCAUCUGACCCCCCUGUGUUAUUCUUUCAUUUCUUACGUACAGAAUAAGAGUAAGAGCCUGAACUAUACGGGAGAGAAAAAGGAGAAACCUGCUGCCGUUGCCACAGCCAUGGCCAGAGUUCUUCGGGAAACCAAGCCAAUCCCUAACCUCAUCUUUGCCAUAGAACAGUAUGAAAAAUUUCUCAUCCACCUUUCUAAGAAGUCCAAGGUGAACCUGAUGCAGCACAUGAAGCUCAGCACCUCACGAGACUUCAAGAUCAAAGGAAACAUCCUAGACAUGGUUCUUCGAGAGGAUGGUGAAGAUGAAAAUGAAGAGGGCACUGCAUCAGAGCAUGGGGGACAGAACAAAGAACCAGCCAAGAAGAAAAGGAAAAAAUAAAUGAAAUGCCUGAGUUAAUGUGAACUUUGGGGCUUCUGCUUCAUUUUUACCCAACAAGCAACAAUGCCCCUUGUCCUGUAGUCCACACCGAUGUUGGCAUCUUGGUUCUGAACCCACUGAAUUCAACUGCACCUUCAGUUAGAAGGAAUCUUCUUGGCAGGUCCUGCUACUGAAAAAUGGCUGGCCUUAGGCAAGCCCUUUUGCAAAAAGCACAGCUGAAAGCCUGAGUUUGGGAGCCUGCACCACCCCGAUGAAGCUCCACGGGAGCAAAUACAGAGCCUCCAGGCAGUGCUAUGGUCCAGGCUGGCUUCGUUUUUCCAAGGAGCCUUUGGUGAGUUCAAUUAUCUGGUAAAUAUCCAGCGCUUCACCUGAAAGAUAGUGCAAAUUGGUUAGGAUGCCACCUCAAGAACUGUAACUGAGAGCUCAGAAGUGAGCAAAGGAGCUUAAUGCUAAGGUCAAAAGGAGAGUGAAAGGUUGAGAACAAUUGCCACGAACGGUAAUGUUACAUGUUAGGAGGGUCUGUUUUCUUUUUAUAUAAGUGUGUCUUAGAUAUAUUUUAAAUAGAAAAUAAGCUUUCUGAUUUACUUGUUUGGUAUUUAAAGCACAGUUUGUUUUUCUGUCACCUAUAGAGUGCAAGAAUGCACUCUAUAGAAUAAAUUAUCUUUAAACAUUUCUUCUGUGGUUGAAGUAGGGGACAGGUACAGGUAGAAUAUUUGAAGCUCUGCUGCCUUCAUUUCUGAAACAUCAUAUCACAUUCACUCUGGACACAGGGCACCUUAUAAACUGAAAUUAGCCUAGAA